CACAGUCCUGCAGAGGGGCGCGCAAAUGAGUUCCUAUUUUGUGAAUCCCACUUUCCCCGGGAGCCUUCCCAGCGGCCAGGACUCCUUCUUGGGCCAGCUGCCCCUCUACCAGGCUGGCUAUGACGCGCUGAGGCCCUUCCCGGCCUCGUACGGGGCGUCGAGUCUCCCGGACAAGACGUACACCUCACCUUGUUUCUACCAACAGUCCAACUCGGUCCUGGCCUGCAACCGGGCGUCCUACGAGUACGGGGCCUCGUGUUUCUAUUCUGAUAAGGACCUCAGUGGCGCCUCGCCCUCGGGCAGUGGCAAGCAGAGGGGCCCCGGGGACUACCUGCACUUUUCUCCCGAGCAGCAGUACAAACCCGACAGCAGCAGCGGGCAGGGCAAAGCACUCCAUGACGAAGGCGCCGACCGGAAGUACACGAGCCCGGUUUACCCUUGGAUGCAGCGGAUGAACUCCUGCGCGGGUGCUGUGUAUGGGAGCCAUGGGCGCCGAGGCCGCCAGACCUACACGCGCUACCAGACACUGGAGCUGGAGAAGGAGUUCCACUUCAACCGCUACCUGACACGGCGCCGCCGCAUCGAGAUCGCCAACGCGCUCUGCCUCACCGAGCGCCAGAUCAAGAUCUGGUUCCAGAACCGCCGCAUGAAGUGGAAAAAGGAAAACAAGCUCAUCAAUUCCACGCAGCCCAGCGGGGAGGACUCAGAGGCAAAGGCGGGCGAGUAGAUGCCUGGGCAGGGACCAGGCCAGCGCUGCAACCUCCUUCGGCUUUGCCCCCUUGCCCUCGCCUGUUCCCCAACUUUUCUCCCCGCCUGCUCCCAUCUGGGGGCUUCCGCAGCUUCAGGGGAGCCCGGAGCUUUGCAAGCGUCUGUGCAUUUAUUUCUUACAAAACAAAACAAAACAAAACAAAACAAAACAAAACAAAACAAAACAAAACCUCACACACAGCCAAUACCAGCGGUGGAGCGGGGCGCACUGCACACACCCA